GCUGGGGAUGGGCAGCCUGGAGAGGCACUGACUUUUGGAAGGGGAGACCAAGACCUGUGACGGAUGGCGCUUCCCAAAGCUUGAUCCUGGGACUCCUGGAAUGGGGGUAGUGGUGGGGUGGAUUGGAGACCCAGGAAGCGGGGUUCAUCCAUGUUGCAGCUCAGUCCCCAACCCCUGGGUCACUGACCAGUAUGCAUACCUGGCCUGUUAGGAACCUGGUGGCACAGUAGGAGGUGAGCAGCAGGCAAACGCAGAACGUUUCAGAGCCAUGAGGAUGCUUCUGCAUUUGAGUUUGCUAGCUCUUGGAGCUGCCUACGUGUAUGCCAUCCCCACAGAAAUUCCCACAAGUGCAUUGGUGAAAGAGACCUUGGCACUGCUUUCUACUCAUCGAACUCUGCUGAUAGCCAAUGAGACUCUGAGGAUUCCUGUUCCUGUACAUAAAAAUCACCAACUGUGCACUGAAGAAAUCUUUCAGGGAAUAGGCACACUGGAGAGUCAAACUGUGCAAGGGGGUACUGUGGAAAGACUAUUCAAAAACUUGUCCUUAAUAAAGAAAUACAUUGACGGCCAAAAAAAAAAGUGUGGAGAAGAAAGACGGAGAGUAAACCAAUUCCUAGACUACCUGCAAGAGUUUCUUGGUGUAAUGAACACCGAGUGGAUAAUAGAAAGUUGAGACUAAACUGGUUUGUUGCAGCCAAAGAUUUUGGAGGAGAAGGACAUUUUACUGCAGUGAGAAUGAGGGCCAAGAAAGAGUCAGGCCUUAAUUUUCAGUAUAAUUUAACUUCAGAGGGAAAGUAAAUAUUUCAGGCAUACUGACACUUUGCCAGAAAGCAUAAAAUUCUUAAAAUAUAUUUCAGAUAUCAGAAUCAUUGAAGUAUUUUCCUCCAGGCAAAAUUGAUAUACUUUUUUCUUAUUUAACUUAACAUUCUGUAAAAUGUCUGUUAACUUAAUAGUAUUUAUGAAAUGGUUAAGAAUUUGGUAAAUUAGUAUUUAUUUAAUGUUAUGUUGUGUUCUAAUAAAACAAAAAUAGACAACUGUU